AGUGGUGUUUGCUUUCUCCACCAGAAGGGCACACUUUCAUCUAAUUUGGGGUAUCACUGAGCUGAAGACAAAGAGAAGGGGGAGAAAACCUAGCAGACCACCAUGUGCUAUGGGAAGUGUGCACGAUGCAUCGGACAUUCUCUGGUGGGGCUCGCCCUCCUGUGCAUCGCGGCUAAUAUUUUGCUUUACUUUCCCAAUGGGGAAACAAAGUAUGCCUCCGAAAACCACCUCAGCCGCUUCGUGUGGUUCUUUUCUGGCAUCGUAGGAGGUGGCCUGCUGAUGCUCCUGCCAGCAUUUGUCUUCAUUGGGCUGGAACAGGAUGACUGCUGUGGCUGCUGUGGCCAUGAAAACUGUGGCAAACGAUGUGCGAUGCUUUCUUCUGUAUUGGCUGCUCUCAUUGGAAUUGCAGGAUCUGGCUACUGUGUCAUUGUGGCAGCCCUUGGCUUAGCAGAAGGACCACUAUGUCUUGAUUCCCUCGGCCAGUGGAACUACACCUUUGCCAGCACUGAGGGCCAGUACCUUCUGGAUACCUCCACAUGGUCCGAGUGCACUGAACCCAAGCACAUUGUGGAAUGGAAUGUAUCUCUGUUUUCUAUCCUCUUGGCUCUUGGUGGAAUUGAAUUCAUCUUGUGUCUUAUUCAAGUAAUAAAUGGAGUGCUUGGAGGCAUAUGUGGCUUUUGCUGCUCUCACCAACAGGUAAGAACCUGCAUGAAAAUCAAUAUGACUGCUAAAAGAACCAACCCAGGACAGAGCCACAAUCUUCCUCUAUUUCAUUGUAAUUUAUAUAUUUCACUUGUAUUCAUUUGUAAAACUUUGUAUUAGUGUAACAUACUCCCCACAGUCUACUUUUACAAACGCCUGUAAAGACUGGCAUCUUCACAGGAUGUCAGUGUUUAAAUUUAGUAAACUUCUUUUUUGUUUGUUUAUUUGUUUUUGUUUUUUUUUAAGGAAUGAGGAAACAAACCACCCUCUGGGGGUAAUUUACAGACUGAGUGACAGUACUCAGUAUAUCUGAGAUAAACUCUAUAAUGUUUUGGAUAAAAAUAACAUUCCAAUCACUAUUGUAUAUAUGUGCAUGUAUUUUUUAAAUUAAAGAUGUCUAGUUGCUUUUUAUAAGACCAAGAAGGAGAAAAUCCGACAACCUGGAAAGAUUUUUGUUUUCACUGCUUGUAUGAUGUUUCCCAUUCAUACACCUAUAAAUCUCUAACAAGAGGCCCUUUGAACUGCCUUGUGUUCUGUGAGAAACAAAUAUUUACUUAGAGUGGAAGGACUGAUUGAGAAUGUUCCAAUCCAAAUGAAUGCAUCACAACUUACAAUGCUGCUCAUUGUUGUGAGUACUAUGAGAUUCAAAUUUUUCUAACAUAUGGAAAGCCUUUUGUCCUCCAAAGAUGAGUACUAGGGAUCAUGUGUUUAAAAAAAGAAAGGCUACGAUGACUGGGCAAGAAGAAAGAUGGGAAACUGAAUAAAGCAGUUGAUCAGCAUCAUUGGAACAUGGGGACGAGUGACGGCAGGAGGACCACGAGGAAAUACCCUCAAAACUAACUUGUUUACAACAAAAUAAAGUAUUCACUACCA